AGUGUGCUGGGUACCAGGCGACUCCGGGACAGGGGGUCUCGGCCGUCGGCGUCAUGGUUUCGCGCGUGCAGCUCCCGCCUGAGAUCCAGCUGGCUCAGCGCCUGGCGGGGAAUGAGCAGGUGACCCGGGACCGGGCGGUGAGGAAGCUCCGGAAAUACAUCGUCGCCAGGACUCAGCGGGCCGCAGGUGGUUUUACGCACGACGAGCUGCUGAAGGUGUGGAAAGGACUGUUUUAUUGCAUGUGGAUGCAGGACAAGCCACUCCUCCAGGAAGAAUUAGGAAGGACUAUUUCCCAGCUCGUUCAUGCUUUUCAGACCACGGAGGCGCAGCACCUGUUCCUUCAGGCCUUCUGGCAGACCAUGAAUCGCGAGUGGACGGGCAUUGACAGGCUGCGCCUGGAUAAAUUCUACAUGCUCAUGCGGAUGGUCCUGAACGAGUCCUUGAAGGUUCUGAAGAUGCAAGGCUGGGAAGAAAGACAGAUCGAGGAGCUGCUAGAGCUGCUGAUGACUGAGAUCCUGCACCCCAGCAGCCAGGCCCCCAACGGUGUGAAGAGCCACUUCAUCGAGAUCUUCCUGGAGGAGCUGACCAAAGUGGGCGCCGAGGAGCUUACGGCAGACCAGAACCUGAAGUUCAUCGACCCCUUCUGCAGAAUUGCUGCCCGGACCAAGGAUUCCUUGGUUUUGAACAACAUCACUCGAGGCAUCUUUGAGACGAUUGUGGAGCAGGCCCCGCUUGCCAUUGAAGACCUCCUGAAUGAACUGGACACACAGGAUGAGGAGGUGGCGUCGGACAGUGAUGAGUCCUCUGAGGGUGGUGAGCGUGGAGACGCGCUGUCCCAGAAGAGGUCUGAGAAGCCGCCCGCAGGCUCCAUCUGCAGGGCUGAACCUGAGGCUGGUGAGGAGCAGGCAGGUGACGACAGGGACAGUGGCGGCCCCGUUCUCCAGUUUGACUACGAGGCAGUUGCUAACAGACUGUUUGAAAUGGCCAGCCGCCAGAGCACCCCUUCUCAGAACAGAAAGCGUCUCUACAAAGUGAUCCGGAAGCUGCAGGACCUGGCAGGAGGCAUUUUCCCUGAAGAUGAGAUCCCAGAGAAGGCCUGCAGGCGCCUGCUUGAAGGGAGGCGGCAGAAGAAGACGAAGAAGCAGAAGCGUCUGCUCAGGUUGCAGCAGGAGAGAGGGAAAGGUGAGAAGGAGCCCCCGAGCCCGGGCAUGGAGAGGAAGAGGAGCAGGAGGAGGGGUGUAGGGGCCGACCCCGAGGCGCGGGCAGAGGCUGGUGAGCAGCCAGGCACAGCUGAGCGGGCCCUGCUCCGAGAUCAGCCCAGGGGCCGUGGCCAGAGAGGGGCUCGCCAGAGAAGGAGGACACCUCGGCCCCUGACCAGUGCCCGAGCAAAGGCGGCCAAUGUCCAGGAGCCGGAGAAGAAGAAGAAACGCAGGGAGUGAUGUGGCCGGGCCAAGGACAGGCAGGGAGGGAGGCCAGGCCUCGCUUGCACCGCGGGACGAGGCUGACCGGGCUGUUCUGUAGACUCAGGACCGUGGCUCCAGAACUCCUGUGCCAGGCGGGAGGGAAGGGCGGCACUGGAGAGAUGGGCCCAUCAUUAGGGGCCAGCAUCCCAGGAACUGGACCUUUCCCCAGAGCCUCCGCCUGUGGCUGUGAUGACCUUGGGCCAGAAGGUCAAACUCCGAAGACUGAAACUCUGCCUGCAGCAGGACUGGCCGCCCCUGCUGUGGGGGGUUCAGAAAAUAAAAUGCCGCGCAGCCCUUGCCAGGGGAAGUGUCGCUUCAGGUGUGUCCUACGGACGUGUGGGAGGUGGCAGGCGCCAGCCUCCGAGCAGUGUGGUGGUUUAUAUUCAUGUUUGUGGAAAAAUCUUGCAAGACAUUUCUCCUUUCACAGAACUGCCCAGGUGUUAACAGGGCUGUCUGGACGGGGCUCUUUUGCUUCCCCCUCAAUCUGGGGUCUAGAGUUGUGCAAGGAAUUCAGCUCCAGUAAGGCCUGGAUUGCCCGGGGUGAGCGUGUGUGUGGUGGGAAGACCUGGCUUCCGCGAGAGCCUUGUUCCUGGAGGCAGGAGCGCCCCGCCAUCCUGGGUACCCGCGGGUCCGCAGGCUGCGCACCUCUUUCCCUCAGCCAGGUCACCCUCAGCGUCCUCCCUGCCCCUCUCCCCUUCACACCUGCUGGAGCCUGUGAGGGAGGUGGCGGGUCCCCACUGUGGCGACGGAGAGCUGACAGUAGCCCAGGGCUUUCCACCUGCAUGGAACAAGGGCCUGUCUGCCGCCAGCGCUGUGGCCACAGCCUGCAUAGGUGACAAGGGGCCGCUGCGUUGGGUUUUGCCCGCAUCUUCUGUUCCAUGGGUGCCCAGCCAGCCAGGCCGUGUGGGAUCCAGCGAGAGGCCAGGGCUUGGAGUGGGCCUGGGACCAGGAAGGACCUCUAGGCUGUGGCUGGCCUUGUGCAGACCCUGGACUGCAUCCGGUUCCCCAAAGCCCUGCUGCAUUCGAGUGUCCCCCAACCCCGGGCAGGUGGCACCUGGUGACACCUCCUUCAGUCCCACUCAGCUGGGCGGCCGGGGCAGGCUUAGGGCACAGUUAGGGGCCAAGGAGAGGGAAGGCCAGGGCCCCUGUUCUAGGGGUUAGGGUUCUUUCCCCAAAGGAACUUAAAAAGACAAGCGUGGCCAGGCACAGUGGCUCACACCUGUAAUCCCAGCACUUUGGGAGGCCGAGGUGGCCAGAUCACCUGAGGUCAGGAGUUUGAGACCAGACUGACCAACAUGGAGAAACCCCAUCUCUACUAAAAUACAAAAUUAGCCAGGCGUGGUGGCACAUGCCUGUAAUCCCAGCUACUCGGGAGGCUGAGGCAGGAGAAUUGCUUGAACCUGGGAGGCAGAGGUUGUGGUGAGCUAAGAUCACGCCAUUGCACUCCAGCCUGGGCAACGAGAGGGAAACUCUGUUUCAAAAAAAAAAAAAAAAA